GCGUCUGCAGGCCCGGCUCCUGCCUCCCAACAACCUCUUUGGACUCAGUGCCUGCCCAGCUCGUGGUGGCCUUGGUCGGCCCACAGCUUCCUCAAGCCAAGCUCCCCAGGCCCAGCUCAGGCCUCACGGUGGCCUCUCCAGGCUCAGCUCCUGCCCUCCGACGGCGUCUCCAGGCCCCAAACGGCCUCCGGUCGGUGGGCUUCUCCAGGCCCAGCUUGGGCCUCCCGGCGGCCUCUGCAGGCCCAAGUGGUCCUGAAGGCAGCCUCUCCAGGCCCAGCUCCGGCCUCCCAGCAAGCAAGCUCUUUUGGCUCAGCUCCUGCCCAGCUCCCGCCGGCUUUUGUAGACCCUGAACUUUCUCCAGCGAAGCUCCUCAGUCCCACCUCCUGCCUCCCGGUGGCCUGUACAGGCCCAGGUCUGGCUGGAGAACAGCCUCUGCAGGCCCCGCUCUUGCCUCCCAGGGGCGUCUCCAGGCCCAGCUCUCGCCUCACGGCGGCCUCCCGGGACCAAGUCCCUGCCUGCCUCCCAGCAGCCUGUGUGCGGCCCAGCUCCUCCGUCACGGUGGCCUGUUGAGGCCCAACUCAUGCCUCUGGCACCCUUUCCAGAGGCGUGAGCCCCUGCCUCACAUUGGCCUCUCUCACGCUGAGGGAGGUCAGCGUGAGCCCCUGCCUCACACUGGCCUCUCUCACGCUGAGGGAGGUCAGCGUGAGCCCCUGCCUCACACUGGCCUCUCUCACGCUGAGGGAGGUCAGCGUGGGCCCCUGCCUCAAACUGGCCUCUCUCACGCUGAGGGAGGUCAGCGUGAGGCCCUGCCUCACACUGGCCUCUCUCACGCUGAGGGAGGUCAGCGUGAGGCCCUGCCUCACACUGGCCUCUCUCACGCUGAGAGAAGUCCUCCCUCACGCUGGCCUGUUGAGGCCCAGUUCAUGCCUCUGUUGGCUUCUCCAGGCCCAGCCCCUGCCUGUUGGCGGCCUCUACCUCAACAGUGGGCCCUCCACGCCCACCUCUUGCCUCGCCGUGGCCUCCUCGGGCCAGGCUCCCGCCUUGGGGCGGCCCCCGCAGGCCCAGCUCCUGCCUCACGGCCCUCUGGAGGCCAAGCUCAUGCGUCAGGGCGGCCUCUCCCGGCCUGGCGUUUGCUCCUUUGCAUGGGCUCCAAAUCCUGCACUUCCUCCAGUCGUUCUCUCCAGGCCCAGCUCUUCCUCCCAGCAGCCUCUGCAGGACCAGACUGUCGUCAAGUAGGCCUGUCCAGGGACAGCUCCUGCCUCCCGGCAGACUCUGCAGGCCCAAGUCGUCCUCAAGUCAGCCUCCCCAGGCCCAGCUCCGGCCUCUCGACGGCCUCUCCAGGUGCAAAAGUUCCUCGAGUCCGUCUCUCCAGGUCCAGCUCCUCCUGUCUCCCAGUGGCCUCUUUCAGCCCAGCCCAGCUCAUGCCUCCCGGCGGCCUUCCCAGGCCCCGCUUCUGACUUUCCG